GCAGAGGACCAGGAAGUUCGCCGACGACGCGCCCGCCCUGGGCCACCGGCGCCGGCCCAAGUUCGCCGGGGGGGCCCGGAGGAAGCUUGGGGGACGCGACGGGGGAACGCGGAAACCCCGGGGAUCUGCAGGCGCGCCCGGGCCGUGUGCCUUCUCUCCGCGUGUCCAAACCGUGUCCCCAGCCGCGCGCCAUGCGCUCUGGGGGCGUGCGCAGCUUCGCGCUGGAGCUGGCGCGGGGCCCGGGCGGCGCCUACCGCGGCGGGGAGCGGCUGUGCGGCCGGGUGCUGCUGGAGGCGGCGGCGCCGCUGCGGGUGCGAGCGCUCGAGGUGAAGGCGCGCGGCGGGGCGGCCACCCACUGGUUGGAGGGUCGCAGCGUGGGCGUCAACGCCGUAUCCAGCGACUACGCGGCCGCGGAGACCUACCUGCGGCGUCGGCAGCUGCUGCUCCGAGAUACCGGGGAGACCACGACGCUGCCUCCUGGGCGCCAUGAGUUCCUGUUCAGCUUCCAGCUGCCCCCGACCCUGGUGACAUCCUUCGAGGGCAAACACGGUAGUGUCCGCUACUGUAUCAAGGCCACCCUGCACCGGCCCUGGGUCCCAGCACGCCGGGCAAGGAAGGUGUUCACUGUCAUCGAGCCUGUGGACAUCAACACGCCAGCCCUGCUGGCACCUCAAGCGGGGGCUCGGGAAAAGGUUGCCCGAUCCUGGUACUGUAACCGUGGCCUAGUCUCCCUUUCGGCCAAGAUCGACCGCAAGGGCUACACCCCAGGAGAGGUCAUCCCUGUCUUUGCCGAGAUCGACAACGGCUCCACACGUCCUGUGCUGCCUCGGGCAGCCGUGGUGCAGACACAGACGUUCAUGGCCCGAGGCGCCCGAAAGCAGAAACGGGCAGUGGUGGCCAGCCUCGCGGGCGAGCCGGUGGGCCCCGGGCAGCGGGCGCUGUGGCAGGGCCGGGCACUGCGGAUCCCCCCAGUGGGUCCUUCCAUCCUGCACUGCCGCGUUCUACACGUGGACUACGCACUCAAGGUCUGUGUGGAUAUCCCAGGAACGUCCAAGCUGCUGCUGGAGCUGCCACUGGUGAUCGGCACCAUUCCCUUGCACCCUUUUGGCAGCCGUUCCUCCAGCGUGGGCAGCCACGCCAGCUUCCUGCUGGACUGGAGGCUGGGGGCCUUGCCGGAGCGGCCUGAGGCUCCUCCUGAGUACUCGGAGGUGGUAGCCGACACUGAGGAGGCAGCCUUGGGGCAGAGCCCCUUCCCGCUUCCGCAGGACCCCGACAUGAGCCUUGAAGGCCCGUUCUUCGCCUACAUCCAAGAGUUCCGCUACCGCCCGCCACCCCUGUACUCUGAGGAGGAUCCAAACCCACUCUUGGGGGACAUGAGGCCGCGCUGCAUGACUUGCUGAACGGCACAGGGACCCCUCGAGGAACAAGGUUGCACACCAGCUUUCAGCCACCAUGACUGUGGGGAGUGGCUGGACCAAGGGCUGACCUCCCCGACUGCAUCAAAGUUGGGGAACCAAGUCUCAGAGUGAGGCGGGGGCCUUUCGGAUAUCACAUGGGACAGAGGAAGAGCCCGGCUGGAAUCUGACUUACCUGGACCGCUGUCCUUGUGAGGCAUUGAAUGCCCAGUGCAGUAUCCGAGAGACUGUUUAAUAACCUGUCUUCCCAGCCAAUUGGUGGUGCUGGAAUCCCCUAGGAGCCUUCAGUCUGGGAGAAACAGAGCCAGACAUAGACAGUUCCAGCAUCACAGAACCAGAAGAAGAGACCUGCAACUGUGAGAGUCCAGACAGGAAGCAGAGAAGGCGUCCUUGCGGAAAGGGCAUUUUAGCUGAGGCUUUGGAGUACGAAUAGGAGCUCAGCAGGCAGACGAAUGAGGAAUAAAGGUCAGAGAAGGUCAGAGCUGAGUGACGUUUGGAAUCCACCCCGUUUAUUGUAGAACUGGGGGUUCAGAGGGCAGGUGCCUCAGAGUUGAGGCCACACAGUGAGGUCUGGUGGGUGAAAGGACCCAGGAACGAGGCGUUCAGGAAAGCAGGUUGUCAGAGCUAUGUGGAGUCUGUGGGUGGCAGGGGCAGCCGCUCCAGCCUUUGAAGACUUUGAAAGCCAGAGAUUCCUGGCGCAGGCUUGGACUUCCUGGGAGCUCCUCCAAGUACCCAGGGGCAUCAGAGCUGCCUGGGUGUUACAUGGCCCAGGGAACCCAGGUUCAGGGUAGGACAGGCAAGACCAGAUACCCAAUGUGCAAAGUGAAAACACUGGGCUCCCUGUUAAACGAUGAAGAAUUCAAGACAGUGACAGCAUUACGUCACCCCUGGGGACAGAGGUCAGCCUAAGGUGACACACGGGGACUACUGUGCUUCCGGAGGCUCCCUGUGUCCUGGAGGAGAAAAGCAUUAGAGGGGGCAGCUGGACAAGCUCCCAACUGCAGAGUCCCAGCCCUGGCUGGGGCAGGGCCCCGGCCUGGGACUCAGCAUUUCUGAUAUGCCUUAAGAAUUCAUUCUGUUUUGUACAAUUAUUUUUUAAAAGUAAACGUGUGGAGAAAGAA